AGUGCCACAGAGCCGAAGCCCGAGCUGCCGCCGCAGCCACAGCCGAGGGCACUAUGGUAAGACGAGCGCGCUGGCCGGGAGGCCGCGGCGAGGCGAGAAAAGCCCCCCGCACGGCCCCGGGAGUGAGGCCGCCAUUUUAACCUGAUUUUGGCCUCCAAGGCUUCUGGAGUUACAGUGAAUGAUGAAGUCAUCAAAGUUUUUAAUGAUAUGAAAGUAAGGAAAUCUUCUACACAAGAGGAGAUCAAAAAGAGAAAGAAAGCAGUUCUCUUCUGUUUAAGCGAUGACAAAAGACAAAUAAUUGUAGAGGAAGCAAAGCAGAUCUUGGUGGGUGACAUUGGUGAUACUGUAGAGGACCCCUACACAUCUUUUGUGAAGUUGCUACCUCUGAAUGAUUGCCGAUAUGCUUUGUACGAUGCCACAUACGAAACAAAAGAGUCUAAGAAAGAAGACCUAGUAUUUAUAUUCUGGGCUCCUGAAAGUGCACCUUUAAAAAGCAAGAUGAUUUAUGCUAGCUCUAAAGAUGCCAUUAAAAAGAAAUUUACAGGUAUUAAACAUGAGUGGCAAGUAAAUGGCUUGGAUGAUAUUAAGGACCGUUCGACACUUGGAGAGAAAUUGGGAGGCAAUGUAGUAGUUUCACUUGAAGGAAAACCAUUAUAAAAUGACAGUCAAGUGCCAUCUGGAUCUUAAGGAGCUUCCAUUUCUCCAGCUCAGUCCAUUGGAAUAGUAUUAGGUUUUGGUUUUUUGUUGUAUUUCCCCCUUUCCACUGGGCCCUUCCAACACAAUGAAUGAAGGAAAUAUCAUUUAUUUAAGCAGCCUAUCAGUGAUUGCCAUUAGACUGUUGAAUACUGUUACUUUUAUAUAGAACCCAAGGAAUGCCUUCCUGUCAUAUUUUAGCCAAAACAACUGGUUAUAUGCCUCCCUUGCAGCAAGCACUACAAUGUAUGUGAUCGUCAAUGUGAAUAGCUUAGAAUACUGCAAAGGAUAAGCUAAUUGAAUGCCUUGAAAGUAUUAUCCACUGGUCAGAUGGUCAACUUUUUUCAGUAUUAUUUAUAGUUGGCACUUGAUUGCAGUUCUGUGAGGCUUGAGCAUUCAUACACCUCACCUGCCUUGGCAAGCCUAUUUUAGUGAUAUGGCAGCACGGAUAUAACACUAUGCAUUAAAAGCACUUUUUGUAAUAAGUUUAAUAUCCUAAAAGGAAUGCCAAUUAAGUUUUGUUAACUGUGUCAUCAACUUAUCCUAGUACCUCAGUGUUCAUUCCUGUUACCUGCAUAUCUUCUUAAAAGAAAUAGCUGUUAUUAAUGCCUUUUUGUUUUCCAUUGAGUGUACACUACUGAAUAAGUGUAGGAGUUUUAUGUUUACCAUGUGAGUCCUGCAACACUAAAGAUAUUUUGAAUAUCAGUCAUGAUGGCAAUUUCUGUAUAAAAGAGCCUUAAAUGGAACAUUGUUUUGAGAUCAAACUCCCCACCCUCACAAAAAUGGCCACGUUGCAAUAAAAAUUGUGGCAUAUUACAGAACGUUGCCUUGUUUUCCUUGGAAAUUUUGCAAAAUGUUAUGUGAAACAACUUCUAGGGUAAAAACAGCUAUUACUAAUCUCUGCACUGGUCAUUUGAGAAUUUUUUUUGUACAGCAUUCAUGUGUGAUAUUUUCCAGAUUUGUUGGAUCUAUUUGGUUUAAAAAGUAUUCUAUCUUAAGGCCAACUAAUAUAAAAUACCAUUGUUAAAGAAUGGUACUUUUAUAAACAUUAGUGUAUUUAUUUCCUAUGUGUUAAUAUGAAGAUCAGAAAUUAUUUUUUGCACUUUGGCAUAAAUACUUUUCAAUAUCUGAUUUGUUCUCUGGAUAAAUUAGCAUAGUUAUUUUUUUAUUCACAUUUACAUUUCUAAGUAGUUGUAUAGUAGAAGCAGGAAGCUCUUAUUGCUUAUUUGGUCGUAAUGAAAAUAAUUUGUAAAAUGUCCUUUAAAAGUUUAAUGAUACUUCUGAUGUUUCGGAACAGUCAUUUCACCUACUAUUUCUGAAUAUAUUUUGCAAAUUGAAUUGGAAUAGGAAUUGAUAAUAGCAGUCUUAAACAUUAGUAGUGGGAUUUGGCUAUGGUCCAGACUGUGCUCCUUAUAGAGAAUUUGAUCUGCUCAGUGUGAGCGGUUUGCUGUUAGCCAGGGCUAUUUAUGGCAAACACAUGCUUUUGUAUCUUGUCAUAGUUAUCCACAAAUGGCAAAACUGGACUUGAUUCUACUGGUAUGCAAAACAGGCAUGCUAGUAAGCAGUCAGUCGUGGCUCAGAACUUAACCCCAUAGCUCAGAGGAAUGCUUUUAGCAGAAAACAGGAAAGAAAAUAUCCCUUAAAAAUUUUUUUUGAAUGUGUGGAAGUAAUUUUAGUAUAAUUAGAUUUUUUCCAUAUUUUUGAAAGAUUUUUCAGAUGUGAACAUUAAAAAUAGGGAUUAAAUGUCUAGGCUUCCAUUUAAAAUUAUAUGAAUGGUUUGGGAUCUUUUUGCACUGAGCAAUUUUAUUUCAGGCUUCCAGCUGUCCCUGUGAGUUAUCCUGGACAUUUCGAUGGUUUUUGGUAAGGCCAAACUCUGAUAAGCAAAACAGAGAAUACUGACGUAUACUUAACCAUAUGUGUAACUGAUACUUGGCACCAUGGAAUUUUUCAUUGAGUUAUUUCCUCAUUCUUUUAAAAAAUAAGGGACUAUAAAUCAGUUAUGUAGUAUCUUUUGUUUUUGUAGCUGAUUCCUUAACUUUCUUGUAUGCCUCUAGUAAUUUCAGAGAUUAAAUAUUGCUUUAAACUGUGAUACUUUGAUUUGCUAGAUUGACAAAACUGAUACUAAUAUAAUUAAGUUCAUCUUUGAAAUACAUCUUUGUGCGUAGAGCCAAAAAAAGAGAUAAAAUUAAUAAUAGUUCACUUGUUAUUUGAGAUUAAUUUGGCAUUUGAAAUGAUCAUUUUAUUUUACAAUCAUUUAUAAUGAAUCAAUGUUCCAGUUAGCUUUAAAAGGUAUACGGUGCUAAUUAGUAAAAUAUUGAAGGCAAUAUUUUACUGCUAGCUUGCAAAGUUAUGAGAGUUUAAAAAAUAAAAUAUAUGAAAAUAUGUAAAGCUGUUGAGAUGUGUUUACUUAUACUUCAGAACAUUAAAAGUUUAAAAACUGGUAUUUCAGAUCAAAGAGGCAUCAUUAUCUUUAUUCUGUUUUUCAGGAUUUUAGUUGGUAAUACUUUCUCAUUUAUCAAUAACAAUUUUCUUUAAAAACUGAGUGUUACAGCAAUUAAUUUUAGCAUUUUCAGACAAAUGGGAACAGUUGGCAUGUGUCCCAAACUGGCUAUCAGCUGUUGUUUUCCAUCAUUAUCUAAAAUAGUGUGGCCAGCAUUGUGUAUUGAAAUGUGCCUUUUUCGUACAUUGGAAGAGAAGCCUCUUACUGGGUUUGAGUUUCUCUGAUACAGAACAUUUGUAGCAGCUAAUUUAUGGAAUCUGGCAAAUAAGCUUUGGGAGGAAAUUCUUUUAAAAGUGUUUUCUUGUUAAGGAAUAAUCUCAACAAUGGUAAAUCAUCAAGAGGUUGAGAAGACUCUUAGGUUUGCCACUCAGAAAAAACAGUCUCAUUUUGCUCUUCAUAGGUCCUGUUUUUGCUUGCACAUUUAAUAGUAGGUGGAGAUGCAAAACAACGUGAAUGUUCAUUUUUUUAUGAAUAGUAUUAAAGCUACUAGAGGUGGGCAGGCAGGUCCCAGUAAAUGUUGCCUUUUUUUUUUUUUUUUUUUGAGACAGGGUCUCACUCUGUUGCCCAGGCUGGAGUGCAGUGUCAAAAUUUCAGCUCACUUCAAACUCAACCUUCCCAGCUCAGAUGAUCCUCCCACCUCAGCCUCCCAAGUAGCUGGGACUACAGGCAUGCACCACCAUGCCUAAUUUUUUUUUUUUUUUUUUUUGUAUCUCUUUUGUAGAGACUGAGUUUGGCCAUGUUGCCUAGGCUGAUCUCCAACUCCUGGGCUCAAGCUGUCCUCUGACCUCCGCCUCCCAAAAGUGCUAGGAUUGCAUGCAUGAGCCACCACUUCAAAAGCUCAAAUACUGCUUUUGAAGACAGCAUGAGUUUAUGGAUGUUCUGUCUCCUUUCAGCCCAUAAAGAAGUCUGAGGCUUUUCUUUUGCUCUGGAACAUCCAACUAAUUGCUUUAUUUCCAUGUAGAAGUAGAGGAAUCAUCCCUCCACUUAAAUUUCCUCUCAUAAUGCAAUUUGGCAAAUUAAAUCUCUAAAUCUCAGUUUUUUAACCCAUAGUAUGGGAACGGUAAUAUCUGUUUACCAUGUUUCCUGAGUACUAAAUAUGGAAAUGGUUUUUGAAAACAGGAAAAUGCUAUGUAAAUGCAAUAAUCUGUUUAAACUAUUCAUUCUUAAUUACUGUAUGUAAGUAGAUAAAUAUUAAAUGUUUUUGUUAAAAGAUGUA